AGGAACCAUACUCCCAUCUGUCAUGGCAGCUGCAGCAAGCCUCACCCAAGGAGAGUCUGGCUGGAGGCCAAACAACACAAAACCAGCACACUUAACAAAAAUAUAACCAAUGACCCUUGCAGAGUCCACUUAACUCCCCUCCACCAGAGCAGGUGCUGGUAUCCACAGCUGAGAGACCUGAAGAUGGAUCACAUCACAGGACUCCUUGCAGACAUUCUCCAGUACCAGCCCAGAGCCUGGUAGGUCUGUUGGGUGGCUAGACCAGUAUUCUAAGUGAAGUAACUCGGAAAUGGAAAACCAAACAUCAUCUGUUCUCACUCAUCAGUAGGAGCUAAGCUAUGAGAACACAAAGACCUGUCCACGCUGAGUUUAUAGCAACUGUCAAUUACGGUUCAGAUUUUCCUACCCCAGCGUGACUUUCCAAAGAGGCUUCUGCUCAUGGAUUUCUGCUCCAGGAAGAUGCAACAGGAAGGUCCUCACAAGAUGGCUGAACAGAUGCAGGUGCUGUGCCUCUGGACUGCCUAGCCUCCAGAACUGAUACAUAUGCAGGAUGUGCAGCUUUGUUACACAGAUGCAAUACCAAGUAAAGACUGCAAAUGACUGUGCCACAGGGAGGAAAAGCAGUCAACCUGUCUUUAGGGACCUGUUCAAAUUUCUGGUGUCUCAGUGGAUGUUGAUUUCUGACAUAAAGCCAUUUGUGCACAUGAGGAAGAUACUGUAGGAGGCAUUUGCUGUGAGCCAGUGUUUGGUCUUUAGCUGAAACAGACAUUUAGCCAUAAACCACCAACCAGAAAGAUCAAUAAGACACGGUUCCUCUUCUGGUGGGCCACAUAAAGGAAGUUGUCAUGUUCCAACUUAAUGUGUGGGUUGAGAGGGAUCUGCACAAACGAGCGUCAUCGGGGAGAAAAAUAUAUCCCAGUCUGCGUGGUCACGGGGAGCUUCCUGGGCAAGCAACAUCUAGACUGGUGUUUGACCAAACUACUGGGCACCAUACCCCAGCCAAGUCAGCAUAUAAUGUGAACCAUCACAGUGGGAGACAUGUCACAAAGUGGUAAGACAGCAAGAAUUGGUGGUCUGGGCUGGAUUCCAGAGAACCUGGACUGUGCCUAUGAAGCACCACUGCCCUGUAGACCUGGGAUAAUAAACACUGAUGCCUAAAGGGACCAGGCAGUAGACCUGACUGGGGAGCUAAGUGAUCUCGUGUGACUCUCUAUGCCUCGUUGCCACCAGCGUGGGCCAUCUCCAGGGGCUCUCAAACCGAUAGAAGACCUUGCGGUGUGGGAAAACAGCUCCAGAGCUUCUAAGCUGAGCGGAUUGUUCCUAGUGAGGAAGUGAUACAAUUUCUUCUUGGGAUUUUCACAAAUGGCAUCAUUGUGGUGGUGAAUGGCAUUGACUUGAUCAAGCACAGAAAAAUGGCUCCGCUGGAUCUCCUUCUUUCUUGUCUGGCAGUUUCUAGAAUUUUUCUGCAGUUGUUCAUCUUCUACGUUAAUGUGAUUGUUAUCUUCUUCAUAGAAUUCAUCAUGUGUUCUGCGAAUUGUGCAAUUCUCUUAUUUAUAAAUGAAUUGGAACUUUGGCUUGCCACAUGGCUCGGCGUUUUCUAUUGUGCCAAGGUUGCCAGCGUCCGUCACCCACUCUUCAUCUGGUUGAAGAUGAGGAUAUCCAAGCUGGUCCCAUGGAUGAUCCUGGGGUCUCUGCUAUAUGUAUCUAUGAUUUGUGUUUUCCAUAGCAAAUAUGCAGGGUUUAUGGUCCCAUACUUCCUAAGGAAAUUUUUCUCCCAAAAUGCCACAAUUCAAAAAGAAGAUACACUGGCUAUACAGAUUUUCUCUUUUGUUGCUGAGUUCUCAGUGCCAUUGCUUAUCUUCCUUUUUGCUGUUUUGCUCUUGAUUUUCUCUCUGGGGAGGCACACCCGGCAAAUGAGAAACACAGUGGCCGGCAGCAGGGUUCCUGGCAGGGGUGCACCCAUCAGCGCGUUGCUGUCUAUCCUGUCCUUCCUGAUCCUCUACUUCUCCCACUGCAUGAUAAAAGUUUUUCUCUCUUCUCUAAAGUUUCACAUCAGAAGGUUCAUCUUUCUGUUCUUCAUCCUUGUGAUUGGUAUAUACCCUUCUGGACACUCUCUCAUCUUAAUUUUAGGAAAUCCUAAAUUGAAACAAAAUGCAAAAAAGUUCCUCCUCCACAGUAAGUGCUGUCAGUGAGAGAGAAGUUGGAUCAGUUCAAAGAACCCAUGAUUCAAUGAUUUACCCAUGCCUGCCACACUUCCCUCAGCCAGACAAAGCAGCCUGUUCAUAAAUAUACAACAUGUCCCCUUCAGGCCUGUUUAUCCAGCCUGAGGUAUUUCUGUGGAUAUGCUACUUUUUCAAGCAGUUAAACUGAUUUUGAAAGCACAACAUAUGUUGAUGGAUUACAUCAAUUUCAAUAUCCUGGUAGUGAUAUUGUACUAUCAUCGUGCAAGUUGUUACCAUUGGGAAAACUGAGUAAAUGGUUCAGGGUCUUUCUGUAUUCCUUCUUACAAAUGCAUUCAAAUCUACAAUUAUUUCAAAAUUAAAAGUUUGAUGAAAAAGAAAAGCACUUGUUUGAACUCGUGAUGUCAGAAGGACACAUGAAUGCUGUAUGGUCCAUGAAUAUCUGACGCCUUGUCUUUGAUGGUUUUUCCUGACCUUAACGGGCUGACUGUUCAUUUCUUGUCUACCUGGAUAUUAUUUCUGUUCUGUCUGUUGGAGUUGCAGGCAGUGGAGCCAUUCUUUCUCCUCAGAUCACAAAGGAAGCAAGGACAAGCAGGCCUUCUCCAUCCUUAUAAGCAUAUUCUCCUACUUCAUCCUGCAGAGAGCCUAGAUGCCAUGGUGACAUGGCCAAUCAACUGAUAAAGGGGAAGACAGAUGGAGGAGGAGGAGGAGUAGAGGACUGAAUGCCUGUUUUCCAUUUCUCCUAGCUGUGCACUCUGAACAGACAAUAACUUGCAAAGAUGUUUUAUUUUGUAUUUGUGUGCCUGACUUUGAGACCCUUUCAACCCAGAGUGGUAAUUUGGAACUCCUCCUGCAUUGCCUGUCUUCCCAAUGAAGCAACAUCAGUAGGUGGGUGGGGCUGGGGGUGUCUCCGUCUGCUUCAAGUCACAAAUGCAUUUUCUGUUUGGUUGAGAUUUUGAAUACUAAGAGAUAGAUAGAUAGAUAGAUAGAUAGAUAGAUAGAUAGAUAGAUAGAUAAAUUAUGGAGAUAGAUAUACUUGUAUAUUUCCAAAACAGCUUCAGAACCAUUUUGCUUCCAGACAAGUAAAUGAAGUAAAAAAUGUUCUUAAGCUCAGCGGUAACUUGUAGUUCAGGCGUGAUGAUGCAAAGCAGGUUUAGGUUUAGAUUUUUCAAUCACCAGUAAUAGGAACCCAAAUACAGCUUUUCUAACCCAAGCCACGCAGGCCUGGUUAUAAUACACCAAUGAAGGAUUUUGCUUCAGGAGAUUCAGGGACGUACUUAUCUUCUUGGGCAUGGGAACUAAGCUCUGAGUGUACUCUCAACUUCCCACAGGUUUCACACUUCAUUCCCCAAGGAGCAAAAUGACAGCCUCCAUCUUCCUGCUAUUUCAUUUUCCCACGUCCCACUAGGUAGGAAGGUUUGUAGCUAAUCACGCACUCAGGAAGCCAGCUGUGGGAAGAUCAGUUGUAUCCUGGGUGUAAUUAUUGCUUCUGAAUGGGGGAAAGGACAAUGAAAAGUCACUUUUCUUUUUCUCAAGUUCAGAGAAUAUUCUGUUCCUUGAAUCUGUGAUACGUGUACCUGAAAGAGUGGGAGCAAUUUCAAACAUUCAGGGAGAAAUUUGUCAUGAUACAACUCUCAUGUGUUUUUUUUUCUGAUACUAAAUUCUGAUUCUAUUUCAUGCAACUCCUGCUUUAAUAACGUUAGCUAAUUAGAUAACUAUUAAGAUAUGACUAGGUUUUUAUACUGUUAUCAAGAAAUGUUUAAAAAAAGAAUUCAUAAUAAAACAAUUCUAAAAACAU